ACUUGCUCCUCCCCCUCCGCCCCUUUAACCUUUAGGGUGCGCGGGUGCAGUAUAUCUCGCGCUCUCUCCCCUUUCCCCCUCCCCUUUCCCCACCCCGGGCGCUCAGGUUGGUCUGGACCGGAAGCGAAGAUGGCGACUUCUGGCGCGGCCUCGGCGGAGCUGGUGAUCGGCUGGUGCAUAUUCGGCCUCUUACUACUGGCUAUUUUGGCAUUCUGCUGGAUAUAUGUUCGUAAAUACCAAAGUCGGCGGGAAAGUGAAGUUGUCUCCACCAUAACAGCAAUUUUUUCUCUAGCAAUUGCACUUAUCACAUCAGCACUUCUACCAGUGGAUAUAUUUUUGGUUUCUUACAUGAAAAAUCAAAAUGGUACAUUUAAGGACUGGGCUAAUGCUAAUGUCAGCAGACAGAUUGAGGACACUGUAUUAUACGGUUACUAUACUUUAUAUUCUGUUAUAUUGUUCUGUGUGUUCUUCUGGAUCCCUUUUGUCUACUUCUAUUAUGAAGAAAAGGAUGAUGAUGAUACUAGUAAAUGUACUCAAAUUAAAACGGCACUCAAGUAUACUUUGGGAUUUGUUGUGAUUUGUGCACUGCUUCUUUUAGUUGGUGCCUUUGUUCCAUUGAAUGUUCCCAAUAACAAAAAUUCUACAGAGUGGGAAAAAGUGAAGUCCCUAUUUGAAGAACUUGGAAGUAGUCAUGGUUUAGCUGCAUUGUCAUUUUCUAUCAGUUCUCUGACCUUGAUUGGAAUGUUGGCAGCUAUAACUUACACAGCCUAUGGCAUGUCUGCGUUACCUUUAAAUCUGAUAAAAGGCACUAGAAGCGCUGCUUAUGAACGUUUGGAAAACACUGAAGACAUUGAAGAAGUAGAACAACACAUUCAAACGAUUAAAUCAAAAAGCAAAGAUGGUCGACCUUUGCCAGCAAGGGAUAAACGCGCCUUAAAACAAUUUGAAGAAAGGUUACGAACACUUAAGAAGAGAGAGAGGCAUUUAGAAUUCAUUGAAAACAGCUGGUGGACAAAAUUUUGUGGCGCUCUGCGUCCCCUGAAGAUCGUCUGGGGAAUAUUUUUCAUCUUAGUUGCAUUGCUGUUUGUAAUUUCUCUCUUCUUGUCAAAUUUAGAUAAAGCUCUUCAUUCAGCUGGAAUAGAUUCUGGUUUCAUAAUUUUUGGAGCUAACCUGAGUAAUCCACUGAAUAUGCUUUUGCCUUUACUACAAACAGUUUUCCCUCUUGAUUAUAUUCUUAUAACAAUUAUUAUUAUGUACUUUAUUUUUACUUCAAUGGCAGGAAUUCGAAAUAUUGGCAUAUGGUUCUUUUGGAUUAGAUUAUAUAAAAUCAGAAGAGGUAGAACCAGGCCCCAAGCACUCCUUUUUCUCUGCAUGAUACUUCUGCUUAUUGUCCUUCACACUAGCUACAUGAUUUAUAGUCUUGCUCCCCAAUAUGUUAUGUAUGGAAGCCAAAAUUACUUAAUAGAGACUAAUAUAACUUCUGAUAAUCAUAAAGGCAAUUCAACCCUUUCUGUGCCAAAGAGAUGUGAUGCAGAUGCUCCUGAAGAUCAGUGUACUGUUACCCGGACAUACCUAUUCCUUCACAAGUUCUGGUUCUUCAGUGCUGCUUACUAUUUUGGUAACUGGGCCUUUCUUGGGGUAUUUUUGAUUGGAUUAAUUGUAUCCUGUUGUAAAGGGAAGAAAUCGGUUAUUGAAGGAGUAGAUGAAGAUUCAGACAUAAGUGAUGAUGAGCCCUCUGUCUAUUCUGCUUGACAGCCUUCUGUCUUAAAGGUUUUAUAAUGCUGACUGAAUAUCUGUUAUGCAUUUUUAAAGUAUUAAACUAACAUUAGGAUUUGCUAACUAGCUUUCAUCAAAAAUGGGAGCAUGGCUAUAAGACAACUAUAUUUUAUUAUAUGUUUUCUGAAGUAACAUUGUAUCAUAGAUUAACAUUUUAAAUUACCAUAAUCAUGCUAUGUAAAUAUAAGACUACUGGCUUUGUGAGGGAAUGUUUGUGCAAAAUUUUUUCCUCUAAUGUAUAAUAGUGUUAAAUUGAUUAAAAAUCUUCCAGAAUUAAUAUUCCCUUUUGUCACUUUUUGAAAACAUAAUAAAUCAUCUGUAUCUGUGCCUUAGGUUCUCCAGAGUGAUGUGGAAUUUUAAAGUGUCUCUCUCUGAUUGCCUCCAAAUAAUAUUUACAAUAUAGCUGAUGAAUGUUACUCCCAUAUGCAAAUUGUUUUCAGUUUUCUGCAUAAAAUCUUUAGCACCACUCAAGUAGAUUUCAUGAAAAGAUUUCAAACUCUAGUUAGUGCUCUAAGAGCAUGGCGUUCCAAGAUGUGUUAUAUUGUUCAAAUAUCAGUCCAUUAGAUAACUUACAACCUCUACAGUAUUUAAGGCAUACAUAUUGUUAUAGGUAGCUUUUGUUUUGCAUCUGACCUCAAAAUGUGUAUUUCAAUAUAAAUAGGGGUAUUGUCAAGAAUAAUUAAUCCUGGAAAAAAAAAUCAGUUUAUGGAUUAAUUUAAGAUAUAUGGCAUCAUAUUUUGGUUUUAGAGAUAAUUUUUCAUUCUAAAGAUUUGAAAUUUGCAAAAGAUGUAAUGAAAGCUGUAUGACAUCAGUAGGGUAUUUUGAACACAUUCUGGAUAGUGAGAAAUAAUAAAAAAUUAUAUUCUAGUUUACUAACAUAAGCACAUUAGAACUCAUAAAAAAGUAUAUAUCAUGAUCCUUGAGGUAAAAUAUCAUUAAGUUUCUGAAAAAAAGUUUAGGAAUUAACAACUAUAUCUAAGUUAAUUAUUCUCUCCCUUAAUUUUUGUGCCAUUUUUCUCUGUUCUGAUUCUUCAUCUCUCUUGAUAAACCUUCACAGCUUUCGUAUUUGGCUUCUGCUUCUGCAACUACCCUUUAGCAUUAUUCACCAGGAUUUCAUUCCCUUCUGUUCUUAUUUUACAUUUUCUUUUUUCUUUUUUUUUAAGAUGGAGUUUCACUCUUGUCGCCCAGGCUGGAGUGCAAUGGCACGAUCUCAGCUCACUGCAACCUCCCCUUCAUGCAUUCAAGCAAUUCUCCUGCCUCAGCCUCCUGAGUAGCUGGGAUUACAGGCAUGUGCCACCAUGCCUGGCUAGUUUUUGUAUUUUUAGCAGAGAUGGGGUUUCACCAUCUUGGCCAGGCUGGUCUUGAACUCCUGACCUCAUGAUCCACCCACAGUGGCCUCCCAAAGUGCUGGGAUUACAGGCAUAAGCCACCACGCUCGGCCUUAUAUUACAUUUUCUUUGUGGACAAUCUCACAUACCCUUGGCUUCUAUCUAUACUACUUGUUCUUAAGCUCUGAACUUUGAGUUAUCUUUUAGCUAGAAAUUACUGCUUCAACUGUAACAUUUUGAAAAUUGAAGUAUUCACUUUUGUGGGGGCAAACUAAGCCUUCUUCUGCAUUCAUUUUUUUGACAAAUGGCACCGCAGACACUUGAUUGCCUAAACAAAGAAUCAGGUAGAUCUCCAUAUCUCUUCUGUAUAACUGACUCAUCAAACAAUCAUGUCAUGUUAAUUUCUACUUCCUAUCUUUCCAUUUGUCCCUUCUUCUCCACUUUCUAUGUUAUAGGCUGAAUUGUGUCCCCUUACAAUUCAUAUGUUGAAAUCUUGUCCCCUGGUACUUCAUAGAAUAAUACUUUAUGUGGAGAUAGGGCCUUUUAAAAGUAAUUAAAGUAAAAUGAGGCUAUUGCGUGAAGCCCAAAUCCAAUAUGACUGGUGUUCUUAUAAGAAGGGGGAGAGACAUCUAGAAUGUGUAUGUACAAAGAAGAGGCCAUGUGAGGAUGCAAUGAGAAGGCAGUGGUCUGCAAGCCAACAGGAGAGGCCUCAGGAGAAUCCAGUGUUGUCAACCCUUUAAUCUUGAGGUUCCAGCUUCCAGAUCUGUGAGAAAAUAAAUUUCUGUUGUUUAAGCCA